GUCUGUGGCCGGAGGCUGAUCAGGUACUGUGGACGGGCGGCGGAGUUCGGGAGACAGGGGCAGGGCGGCAUCGGGGAGCUGCGGGACGGGGCGGGGAGGAGGCCCGAGGUCUGAGCCACCCGUGAGGUCUCGGCGCGGAGGCCUGGACAGCUGGGGGUGGCGGCGUUGGUCUCCCGAACUGGAGGGAGGCCGGGCCUUCCCGGGCUGUGGUGGGCGCCCGCGCCCCGUGGAAGGCGGAGGCGUGAGUCGGGGCGUCAGAGACGUUGCCAUUCUUUGUCAGCGGAAAAGAUCGUCGUCUGCGCACAGUCACCUGAGGUUUAGGAACUCGUGGAACUGGAAACCGAGUCGCAGGAGACUAAGAGUUGCGAGUCUCCCCUUAGAGAAUUCAGAAACAAGCGUAGACAGCAUCGUCAGAAACACGAGCGUGACGACACCGGCCUCCCCGUGCCGAGUCCACGCGUGUGACGCGGGUGCAUACACCUGCGUCCGUGCAAGAGGGUGACAGCAACACACUCAAGGCGCUUCUCCUGGGAAUGGAGCAGGAGAAGAGAUGGGGAGCAUCGCAUAGAUGGAACUAGACCUUUUUCUUGGGUUGGAUGAUGUGUUCCCGCGUCUACUACAUGUGUUCUAGAACAGAUCAGACAUUUUGUAAUGAUGCCUGAAAUAAACACUAACCACCUCGACAAGCAACAGGUUCAACUCCUGGCAGAGAUGUGUAUCCUUAUUGAUGAAAAUGACAAUAAAAUUGGAGCUGAGACCAAGAAGAAUUGUCACCUGAACGAGAACAUUGAGAAAGGAUUAUUGCAUCGAGCUUUUAGUGUCUUCUUAUUCAACACCGAAAAUAAGCUUCUGCUACAGCAAAGAUCAGAUGCUAAGAUUACCUUUCCAGGUUGUUUUACGAAUACGUGUUGUAGUCAUCCAUUAAGCAAUCCAGCCGAGCUUGAGGAAAGUGACGCCCUUGGAGUGAGGCGAGCAGCACAGAGACGGCUGAAAGCUGAGCUAGGAAUUCCCUUGGAAGAGGUUCCUCCAGAAGAAAUUAAUUAUUUAACACGAAUUCACUACAAAGCUCAGUCUGAUGGUAUCUGGGGUGAACAUGAAAUUGAUUACAUUUUGUUGGUGAGGAAGAAUGUAACUUUGAAUCCAGAUCCCAAUGAGAUUAAAAGCUAUUGUUAUGUGUCAAAGGAAGAACUAAAAGAACUUCUGAAAAAAGCAGCCAGUGGUGAAAUUAAGAUAACGCCAUGGUUUAAAAUUAUUGCAGCGACUUUUCUCUUUAAAUGGUGGGAUAACUUAAAUCAUUUGAAUCAGUUUGUUGACCAUGAGAAAAUAUACAGAAUGUGAAUAUGUAGGUAAAUGAUUACAGAAAAAUUUAUCUGCUUAACAAACUUAGAAUGACUUUUUCCUUUUAAAUUUAGUUCUAUCAUUAAUUUAUCAUUAAAUUUAGUUCUAUCAUUUGGUACUAUCAUUAAUGUAUUAUAUACACUGAUACUUUAAAACUUGUGUGGAAAAAACUAACUUAUAAUUUUGUAUCACACACCCUGGAUAUGUGUUCUGUUUCUAAGCGACAUUUGUGAGAGAUUAUUGUAAAAUGAGAGCGAGCAAAUAAAACUUAAUUUAAUCUUUGCAGAUACAUACUUAUGGGAAAUUUGAACAAAUGAGUGAAACUCUGUUUUUAGUAGGCUGUGAUAAACAUUUCCGGAGCACUUGCAGAGGACUUGCUAUUUGCCAGGUGCUUUAUGUAUCAUUAAAUUUUUCUCAUAGUUCAGAAAAAUGUGCAAAGGAAACUAUUGUCUCGCUCCUUCAAAACAGUCUUAAUUAACUUUCAUAUUAGCAGAUUAAACUAGCAGAGCAGGUUCAAGGGAAAUUAAAUGAUAUGGACCCUAAUUUGUAUCAUUCUGAGUUGAUUGUGUGGUUUAUUCAUUCUGGAAACAUGUUGAUACUUACAGUCAGCCACUGCUUUUGAUAAGUGAUAUUGAUUAGGUUGAAUCUUCUUGUAAAUAGUAUUUACCAGUUAGCAAAGUCUGUGUUUUCAGAAUUACAGUGAGCACAGAGGUGUUCAUAAAAUGGGAAUUGAGUCCCACUCGGUAAGAGUUGCUUAAACUUGACACUGUUGACAUUUGGGCUGGAUAAAACCCCUGUGGUGGGGUCUGUGCUGUGCAUUGCAGGAUGGUGAGCAGCGUCCCUCUCAUGUGACACCCACAGUUAUGCCGGAUGUUGCCAGAUGCCCCUAGGGGACAGAGUCAACCCCCAACUGAGGACCACUGUCCUACAGAGUCAGGAAAUAUUGUAGGGAGAAAAAAAUAACAACAACAAAGGCCUGUGUUAAUGUUAAAUAGAUGAGAUUAUGGAAUGUGUAUAUUAAUGUUAAAAAUUGUACCUUGAUCAAUGUACUUUUUAUAAACUUGCCAUAGAUAUCUCAGAUUUGAAACCUCAAGACAGAUUUAUUAUUCUUAAAUGCUGUAUGAUAAUGAAGAAAAAUAAAAAUUUAUUUCUUGCAAAGUUAAAUGUUUGUUAAAUUCAAUAGAAUGACUCAUUUAUGGUUAACUUUGGGCAAUUUAUAAUUUCAGACAAGACUGUUUAGCAAGUAUUUUAUUGAAAAGUAAAAAAAAUUGCAAUUUAAUACUGUGUUUAGUUUGUUAAAAUUUUGAUACACUAAUAGGAUAUUGCCUGUAUAGUUUCCGUUGCAUUUAUAAUAUUGUUUCUAAUUUUUUUAGUUUUAUUUUCUAGGAAGUUUUAGGCUGAAAGCCACAUAUAAUUAGUUAUGUGAUAACUAUGAGUUGCCAUGGCUACUGAAUUGGACAUGGGACCCUUAGACUGCUACCCAGCACCUUGUUAAGUACUUAGCAAGAGUUAGAUACUACUGUUGUAAUAUUACUAGGAUGCCAUCCAGAAAAUGUAAGGAAUGUCUUUUGACCUGAUAAACUCCUUAGAACUCCUUCAUCUUUUAUAAAGAGGAGUAUCCCUCUCCUAGAUAUAGCUGCUUCUGACCCCAAAGGCAGAUGUGUUGGUUUUCAACUAGAAAGCUAAAUGGUACCUAUAAAUUUUUUUUUUCUUAAACUGUUUUAAACUCUUAAUCUUCAAAAUAUAUACUUCUUUGAUUCUGGUCAAACCAUUGCCAACUCCUUUAAGGACAAAGUAGAGGUGGCCUUCUAAUAAUUGCUGAUUCUGUUUCCCUACCUAUAUUAUCAAGAGAACAAGACCAAAACAGAAAAUGGUAUAAUAGGAAGGAAGGCACAUUUUCUUCUUACUUGGCCCUGGCACCUGGGGACAAGUCCAGGUCGUACCCGCAGUGCAUCCCUGUGGGAACUGCCCUCCACCUGCUCCCUGGGGACACGUCCAGGUCGUACCCGCAGUGCGUCCCUGUGGGAACUGCCCU